AUUGUGCCUGCGCUGCCAGCAGCCAGGAGCCAGGAGCCAAGAGCAGAGCGCCAGCAUGAACUUGGGGGUCAGCAUGCUGAGGAUCCUCUUCCUCCUGGAUGUAGGAGGAGCUCAAGUGCUGGCAACAGGCAAGACCCCUGGGGCUGAAAUUGAUUUCAAGUACGCCCUCAUCGGGACUGCUGUGGGUGUCGCCAUAUCUGCUGGCUUCCUGGCCCUGAAGAUCUGCAUGAUCAGGAGGCACUUAUUUGACGACGACUCUUCCGACCUGAAAAGCACGCCUGGGGGCCUCAGUGACACCAUCCCGCUAAAGAAGAGAGCCCCAAGAGCCCACGUCCUCAGGGACGGUCCUGCCUUGGGACCUUUGCACUUGCUGUUUUCUGUAAUUGGAAUGCUCUUUGCCAGAAAGCUGCAAGCCUCGACCCUCUUUUCCUUCAAAUCCCUGCUUCAGUGUCACCACUGCAUCAUGGAGGGCCUAUUUAAGGCGAAACCACAAUUUCUCCAAAAGCAUCUGGCCAGAUCUGUGCAAAUUCACCAACUACAGAAAGUGAAAAGUUUCCCAAAAUAUGCCUAUUAACCUCGAGGAAUGACUUCUCUUUUUGUCAUCAAAGUGGAUGAAGUUUUGUUUGCCUUGGGUUUGGCAGGCAGAAAACAACUUCCAGGUUGAGCUCUCCCCUUUACCCAGAAGCCACUGGCCUUCAGUUCCUUUCUAUGUUGCACAAGGAAGUGGCCCACCUUGCAGGCUUUGCUGAUGAGCUUUUAUACCUGUUUAAUUGUGUGAAUUGCAUAAACACAUGCAAUCAUUAGAGUAUAGUUGCUCUCUCAAUAAGUCUUCCAGAUGGUUCUCUUCCUUUCCAGAGAUGCACAGGUGAUUGAGCUGUAGGUGAGCAGUGACGUGAAGAGGGGUUCUAGCCCCGUGGAAAACAGCCCAUGGUUAACAUCUCAGGAUGUUCUGCAUUCAAACACCCAAGGCUGGUAAUGAACUUUCACAUGGACUGAAUAUUGGAGGCAAAUAAUAGAAGGAAUAGAAUAUACAGUGCCUCUGUCCUGAAGGAAAAUAUCAUGCCUCUUCUGGAAGAAACGGACUGCACAGAGGAAGGAUUGAGCAAUUUAGCCUGCAGUGGAAGAAGGUGGACACCAAAAGCUUCACCCUGUGUUGGAGCUGUUCAUGCUUCCAUGAGGCCAUGGUGUCCAUGUCCGUGGAACCUACCACAGAAAAUGGCUCAUGAAAAGGGGAAUCCGACCCAACACACAGCUUCCUACACACUGCCAUCUUAUCAACAGUUAGGCACUACUUUGUAGAACGAUUAGCUUCACCCUCUUAGCUGCCAGGAGAUCCCUUCUUAAAGAUGGACUAUGUGAAGAUUCGGGAGUCCUGAAACAUGGGGACUCCGGGAUGGUCUCUAGCCCUAUCGAUGAUGAACACUGGCCUUCUGGAGGGGAAAUGGCAGUCUGGGCUGGCGUGGUAGGAAGGGCUUUGGUGUUCAUGGAAUGGGCCUGCUGCUCUCAGACCUUCAAAGGAUGGAACCAACGAAGGACCAAAUGAGAAAGCAGAUGCUGUGCCUUGCAGAGGGCCAUGAAUGUCAGUUAUUAUUUUUCUCCUUAUACAAUUAUUUUGUGGUUAUUAUUACAAUGUACAUGGCUGUUGCAUAGAAGACAUGACUGGUGGAGGCUGAGGAAAGCCAUGACAUUCUACAAUUGCCAUCAGGCUAAGGCCCCGUGAGCAUUUCUCUCCCUUGUAAUAUUAACCCUGUAUUUCUGGGAUCACAUCACGGAAUAUUCUUUGCCUUUCCACUUUCCAGGAAAUCUCUCGGACUGGGCUACCCUCCUUGUGUGUGAUGAAAGAUGAGCUAUAUUUCAGAACAAAGUGCUGUGUUGUCAUGAUUUGCCUGGACUCCCAGGGCGUCUCUUACCCAACUUGAUAACGAUGCUGUUCAUUAGCAGCCUUUGUUAACUGAUAACCAAGAGCGGUAAUGUGAUACUCAUAAGCAAUUUUCUGUGUGUAGGAUAAAAUAAACCAUCUUGUAUGGGA